CCUUUCCUCUCAGUCCUGCCAUCUAGCUGCCUUGGGUCUCGCGCUCCGCAGAGCGUUCCGACACUCUCCGGCCUCGUUCUGCCGCCUCCGCGCGCUCUCCCCGUGCGGCCACCGCGCCCCCCAAGCUUGCCUCCUUCUUGCCGGACUUGGGGCCGCGCGCCCUGACUCCUUCCCCUCCCGCGGACCCGCGCACUCCCGGCGCGGCCUCUCCCCCACGCAGGCCACCGUGCACUCUGUGGCCUCCCCCUCCUUCCCCGCUCUCCUCGCGCUUCUCUGGCUCCCUAGCUGUCGCGCUCUCCUCGGCGAGCGCGCUCCCGGCCCGCGCGCUCCGGGCUCCGGUUUCUCCCGGCUCCUGUCAGUGCGGUGACUGCGCUGGGAAACAUGGCGACCGAGGGAAUGAUCCUUACUAACCACGACCAUCAAAUCCGUGUCGGAGUCCUUACAGUGAGUGAUAGUUGCUUCAGGAAUCUUGCAGAAGACCGCAGUGGGAUAAAUCUCAAAGAUCUCGUACAAGAUCCUUCUUUGUUGGGUGGGACUAUAUCAGCAUACAAGAUAGUACCAGAUGAAAUAGAAGAAAUCAAGGAAACCCUGAUAGAUUGGUGUGAUGAAAAGGAACUUAAUUUGAUAUUAACAACUGGAGGAACAGGAUUUGCACCACGAGAUGUCACUCCAGAGAAAUUCCCAACAUUCCCAUUUUGUGGGCUCCAGAAAGGGGCCACAAAAGAAGUAAUAGAACGGGAAGCACCAGGGAUGGCCCUGGCAAUGCUGAUGGGAUCACUUAAUGUUACACCUCUGGGCAUGCUCUCUAGGCCUGUAUGUGGAAUCAGAGGGAAAACGCUCAUAAUUAACCUGCCAGGUAGCAAGAAAGGAUCUCAGGAAUGCUUUCAAUUCAUACUGCCAGCUCUACCUCAUGCCAUUGACCUUUUACGUGAUGCCAUUGUAAAAGUAAAGGAGGUGCAUGAUGAACUUGAAGAUUUGCCUUCCCCACCUCCCCCUCUUUCCCCUCCUCCUACUACCAGCCCCCAUAAACAGACAGAAGACAAAGGAGUUCAAUGUGAGGAAGAGGAAGAAGAGAAGAAAGACAGUGGUGUUGCUUCAACAGAAGAUAGUUCCUCAUCACAUAUAACUGCAGCAGCCAUUGCUGCCAAGAAGCAUCCAUUCUACACCAGUCCUGCUGUUGUCAUGGCACACGGUGAACAGCCCAUCCCUGGUCUCAUCAAUUAUUCCCAUCAUUCAACAGAUGAACGGAUUCCAGACUCCAUCAUUUCUCGUGGUGUUCAGGUGCUCCCACGAGACACAGCCUCCCUCAGCACUACUCCUUCAGAAUCGCCUCGUGCUCAGGCUACAUCUCGCCUCUCUACAGCUUCCUGCCCAACACCAAAACAAAUUAGACGGCCGGAUGAAAGCAAAGGAGUUGCUAGUAGAGUUGGAUCCCUCAAACUCCAUCGAAAGCUGGAGGAGCUCAGAGAUCACCUAGAAGGCAAUGUGAAAGGAUACUCUCUCAGAGUAAAUGUCCAGUCCAGGUGCAGCAGCAAGGAGAACAUUCUCAGAGCCAGUCACAGUGCUGUCGAUAUCACCAAGGUGGCUAGAAGACAUCGCAUGUCUCCUUUUCCUCUGACAUCUAUGGACAAAGCCUUUAUCACAGUCCUGGAGAUGACUCCGGUGCUUGGGACAGAAAUCAUCAAUUACCGAGAUGGAAUGGGGCGAGUCCUUGCUCAAGAUGUAUAUGCAAAAGACAAUUUACCCCCCUUCCCAGCAUCAGUAAAAGAUGGCUAUGCUGUCCGAGCUGCUGAUGGCCCAGGAGAUCGUUUCAUCAUUGGGGAAUCCCAAGCUGGUGAACAGCCAACUCAGACAGUAAUGCCAGGACAAGUCAUGCGGGUUACAACAGGUGCUCCAAUACCCUGCGGUGCUGAUGCAGUAGUACAAGUGGAAGAUACCGAACUUAUCAGGGAAUCAGAUGAUGGCACUGAAGAACUUGAAGUGCGAAUUCUGGUGCAAGCUCGGCCAGGCCAAGAUAUCAGACCCAUCGGCCAUGACAUUAAAAGAGGGGAAUGUGUUUUGGCCAAAGGAACCCACAUGGGCCCCUCAGAGAUUGGUCUUCUGGCAACUGUAGGUGUCACAGAGGUUGAAGUUAAUAAGUUUCCAGUGGUUGCAGUCAUGUCAACAGGGAAUGAGCUGCUAAAUCCUGAAGAUGACCUCUUACCAGGGAAGAUUCGAGACAGCAAUCGUUCAACUCUUCUAGCAACAAUUCAGGAACAUGGUUACCCCACGAUCAACUUGGGUAUUGUAGGAGACAACCCAGAUGACUUACUCAAUGCCUUGAAUGAGGGUAUCAGUCGUGCUGAUGUCAUCAUCACAUCAGGGGGUGUAUCCAUGGGGGAAAAGGACUAUCUCAAGCAGGUGCUGGACAUUGAUCUUCAUGCUCAGAUCCAUUUUGGCAGGGUUUUUAUGAAACCAGGCUUGCCAACAACAUUUGCAACUUUGGAUAUUGAUGGUGUAAGAAAAAUAAUCUUUGCACUACCUGGGAAUCCUGUAUCGGCUGUGGUCACCUGCAAUCUCUUUGUUGUGCCUGCACUGAGGAAAAUGCAGGGCAUCUUGGAUCCUCGGCCAACCAUCAUCAAAGCAAGGUUAUCAUGUGAUGUAAAACUUGAUCCUCGUCCAGAAUACCAUCGGUGUAUACUAACUUGGCAUCACCAAGAACCACUACCUUGGGCACAGAGUACAGGUAAUCAAAUGAGCAGCCGUCUGAUGAGCAUGCGCAGUGCCAAUGGAUUGUUGAUGCUACCUCCAAAGACAGAACAGUACGUGGAGCUCCACAAAGGCGAGGUGGUGGAUGUCAUGGUCAUUGGACGGCUAUGAUGGUCACCAGCAGGAGAAAGCUUUGAUGCAUGUCCACAUAUCAUUGACUGUAUCCUGUAAUAUGCAACGGCACAGCUAGUUUUCCCGAUUUGGAUAAAAGUUGAUCUGUAUAGUCAACAUCUUGAACUAUAUUUCAAAUGAAUUUAAAUAUCUUUUAAAGAAAAAAACACCUAAAAAUAAAUCUUAACAGAAAAUUCUGUUCUGAUUAUAUCAAGGCAAAUUUUUCCUUUCUUGCAAAUUGCUUUGUGUGUUCAAUGCUAGGUCUGAUAGCGAUAGCUUUUAGUAGACAGCGGUAGGUGCCUGCAGAACUUGUGUUUUUCUCAUCUUUAAAAUACAACUACUUAUGCUCUUAAAUCAAGGCUGUCUGCUUAUUUAUACUAGCGUAGGCAACACUUGGAUUUCCCUUCUUAGUAUGCUUCAUAACUGCUUUACAGAGAGCUUUUGCUUGUUCUUUCUCAUGUAUCUCGUGUUUAUGUGCACAGUGCCAAAAGAAGACUGACUGGGUGGAGGCUCUGCCUUGCCUCAAGAACCAUCCCCUGCAGAGCAUCCAGGGAGGUUUCUCGCCCCAAUAGCCUCACGGCACAGUACUCUUGGGCAGUAACUGGACACCUUUUAUUUGAAGAAACAAACUGAAGAAAAAAUGCUUCCUUAAGUGCUGACAGCCUUUUUAACCAAUACAUUUAAAAUUGUACAGAACAAAAAAAUAAAAUCAAAGACUGAUCUUGUACAGAUAUUAGUGUUACCAGCAUUCAUGUGGAAAUCAAGAGCAAAGACAAAAUAAUGUUAAACAAUUCUGUACCAUAACAUUUUCUGUAAUGAUACUGAAACUUAAUGAAUAAAAAAAUUCCUUGAUCAUUAUUUAAAAA